CUUUUUUCACCUCGUCUGAAAUGGCUGCCUCCCAGUGUCUCUGCUGCUCAAAAUUUCUCUUCCAGAACUGGGAAAGCCAGGUUUGUUGACAUCUUUAAAGAACAUGGAACAGCCAAGUAAGGAUUUCUGUGACUCUCAUAAGAAAUCUUCAAAGAGCUCAACCUACUCAGCAUCAAGUUACUCUUCUUCAGGAAAGAGACAGAACCUCGCCUGUUUCCUCACAAACCCACACUGUGGCAGCCUUGUUAAUGCAGAUGGCCAUGGUGAAGUGUGGACAGAUUGGAAUAAUAUGUCCAAGUUUUUCCAGUAUGGAUGGCGAUGCACCACUAAUGAGAAUACCUAUUCAAACCGUACCCUGAUGGGCAACUGGAACCAGGAAAGAUAUGACCUGAGGAAUAUCGUGCAGCCCAAACCCUUGCCUUCCCAGUUUGGACACUACUUUGAAACAACAUAUGAUACAAGCUACAACAACAAAAUGCCACUUUCAACACAUAGAUUUAAGCGAGAGCCUCACUGGUUCCCAGGACAUCAACCUGAACUGGAUCCUCCCCGAUACAAAUGCACAGAAAAGUCAACUUACAUGAAUAGCUAUUCAAAGCCUUAAAUUGGGCAUCACUCAGGAUGUGUAUAAGAUCUUAAUAUUGACUAGUUUCACAUCCAGGUUUCUAAGAAAUGAUAAGAUACUUCACUUUUCCAGAGUGAAAUGUAGGAGGGAGCACAUUCUAAGUACAGCUAAAAAUUUAGCUCACUGUAACACAGUUUCACUCUCUGAAUAAAUAAAGCAAAAAACACAGUAAAUAUUCUUUAUCCCUUUUUUUGUUGUUGUUUUAACCAAGAUUUAAAUGUCAAAUUUAAUACAGCAACUCAGUUCUACAUUUGGGGUGUUGUAGAAGGGCCUUAAAAAGAAUUAUUUUAGGCCAGGCACGGUGGCUCAUGCCUGUAAUCCCAGCACUUUGGGAGGCCGAGGCAGGUGGAUCACGUGAGGUCAGGAGUUCGAGACCAGCCUGACCAACAUGGUGAAACACUGUCUCUACUAAAAACACAAAAAUUAGCUGAGCAUGGUGGCUCACGCCUGUAAUCCCAGCUACUCAGGAGGCUGAGGCAGGGGAAUCGCUUGAACCUGAGAAGUGGAGGUUGUGGUGAGCUGAGAUCAUGCCACUGCACUUUAGCCUGGGUGACAGAGCGAGACUCUGUCUCAAAAAAAAAAAAAAAAAAAGAAUUAUUUCUCUGAAGUCUACAACCACUGUGGUCUUCCCUUCCUUCUGUCGUAGCAAGACCUCAGAAUCUAGCAUAACUUAGGCUAGGUUUGGCUAGAUGCUUUCUGGGUAUAAGCCAGAGUCGUAUAGUGCAACUUUGCUGUGACCUUAGUGAACAUCCCCUCUUGAGGACUACAAAAACAAACGUAACUUUUUAAAAUUAUUAUGGAGAAUUUUACGUAAAACAAAAGUAGACAGGCUAGUCUAAUGAACUCCCAUGUAUCAUUACCCAGCAUCAACUAUUUAUGACUAAUCUUACCUACUUCUACUUUGUCUUAUUGAAUUAAUUUUGGAGCAGAUCUUAGAAAUAGAAUUUAAUCUAUAAAAAUCUUGGUGGGCUGGGUGCGGUGGCUCAUGCCUGUAAUCCCAGCACUUUGGGAGGCUGAGGUGGGUGGAUCACCUGAGGUCAGGAGUCCAAGACCAGCCUGGCCAAUGUGGUGAAACUCCAUCUCUUCUAAAAAUACAAAAAUUAGCUGGUCUUGGUGGCGGGCGCCUGUAAUCCCAGCUACUUGGGAGGCUGAGGCAGGAGAAUUGCUUGAACCCAGGAAGCAGAGGUUGCAGUGAGCUGAGACGGUGCCAUUGCUCUCCAGCCUGGGCGACAAGAGCGAAACUCCGUCUCAAAAAAAAAAAAGAAAAGAAAAAGAAAAAAAAAAUCUUGGUAUACUGGCUGGGCACAGUGGCUCACACCUAAUCCCAGCACUUUGGGAGGCUGAGGCAGGAGGAUAGCUUGAGGCUGGGAGUUCAAAACCAGCCUGGGCAACAUAGCAAGACCCCAUCUCUACCAAAAAAAAUUUUUUUAAAGAUUUCAGUAUAUUUCUCAAAAAGAUAAGGACUGUCAAUUGUCUACUCCCCCCCAACAAAGGUCACUAAGGAAACCUGUUGACUAAACAAAGCUCAUUAAACCUAUUGUAGUGUAGCAAAGGAGACCAUCAACUUGACACAGAGUCUUGGUAAUGAUUCAAAGGGAGGAUGUUAGAGUAAGGUAUUUAUAAGGAUUUGAGAUAAGGGUCCAACUGGUUUAAAAUGAGUCAAAAUAGGGAACUAGUAGAGACUGAGAAAGGGUUGUGAAUAGCUUAGGUUUGGUAAACUUAGGAAAUCAACAGUCUUAAUUUUAAUAUGGUUAAACUGAUUAGUAUUUCCUAUUUUUUUAUCUACUGUGUAAGAAGACACUAUAAUAUAUGGGCAUUACUGAGAGAUACUGCCCAUAUGUUGUCCUCGUAAGCAAGGAGAUAUUUUUUAUCUCCCAUAUAUUACCUCUCAAACCUUUGUUACUUUAGUUUCGAGAUAUAGAUCCAGAAUUUAUGUUGUUACUCAGUAGUGAGGAAGUUUCUUUUUUUUUUCUAAAUGGCUAUCAAGUUGUCCCACCAUUAGUUAUUGAAAAGACCAUAAUUUUUUCACUCCUAUUCAAUGCCAUUUUUAUUGUAAAUAAACUAUGUACAUGUA